AGAAUAAAAAACAUUUGCCAAGACCUCAUGCCCUUUUAGUAAACGAAUGUUUACUGCCACCUCCAGAGAAGCUCACUGCUGAGGUCCUAGGAAUCAUUUGCAUUGUCCUGAUGGCCACUGUGUUAAAAACAAUAGUUCUUAUUCCUUGUAUUGGAGUACUGGAGCAGAACAAUUUUUCCCUGAAUAGAAGAAUGCAGAAAGCACGUCAUUGUGGCCAUUGUCCUGAGGAGUGGAUUACAUAUUCCAACAGUUGUUAUUACAUUGGUAAGGAAAGAAGAACUUGGGAAGAAAGAGUUUGCUGGCCUGUGCUUCGAAGAACUCUGAUCUGCUUUCUAUAGAUAAUGAGGAAGAAAUGCUACUGGGGAUAAAGGAAGGAGAAAUAAGUCAACUAAAAUUUGAGCACCUGCUAAUAGGUAUGUGUGGGGACUUCCCAGUUGGCUGUAAGUUGCCAUUUGAACUAAACGAAAUAGGAAUCCUUUGUGCAUUGAAGACUUUAGAUUCCUCUCUGCGGUAGACGUGCACUUAUAAGUAUUUGAUGGGGUGGAUUCGUGGUCGGAGGUCUCGACACAGCUGGGAGAUGAGUGAAUUUCAUAAUUAUAACUUGGAUCUGAAGAAGAGUGAUUUUUCAACACGAUGGCAAAAGCAAAGAUGUCCAGUAGUCAAAAGCAAAUGUAGAGAAAAUGCAUCUCCAUUUUUUUUCUGCUGCUUCAUCGCUGUAGCCAUGGGAAUCCGUUUCAUUAUUAUGGUAACAAUAUGGAGUGCUGUAUUCCUAAACUCAUUAUUCAACCAAGAAGUUCAAAUUCCCUUGACCGAAAGUUACUGUGGCCCAUGUCCUAAAAACUGGAUAUGUUACAAAAAUAACUGCUACCAAUUUUUUGAUGAGAGUAAAAACUGGUAUGAGAGCCAGGCUUCUUGUAUGUCUCAAAAUGCCAGCCUUCUGAAAGUAUACAGCAAAGAGGACCAGGAUUUACUUAAACUGGUGAAGUCAUAUCAUUGGAUGGGACUAGUACACAUUCCAACAAAUGGAUCUUGGCAGUGGGAAGAUGGCUCCAUUCUCUCACCCAACCUACUAACAAUAAUUGAAAUGCAGAAGGGAGACUGUGCACUCUAUGCCUCGAGCUUUAAAGGCUAUAUAGAAAACUGUUCAACUCCAAAUACGUACAUCUGCAUGCAAAGGACUGUGUAAAGAUGAUCAACCAUCUCAAUAAAAGCCAGGAACAGAGAAGAGAUUACACCAGCGGUAACACUGCCAACUGAGACUAAAGGAAACAAACAAAAACAGGACAAAAUGACCAAAGACUGUCAGAUUUCUUAGACUCCACAGGACCAAACCAUAGAACAAUUUCACUGCAAACAUGCAUGAUUCUCCAAGACAAAAGAAGAGAGAUCCUAAAGGCAAUUCAGAUAUCCCCAAGGCUGCCUCUCCCACCACAAGCCCAGAGUGGAUGGGCUGGGGGAGGGGUGCUGUUUUAAUUUCUAAAGGUAGGACCAACACCCAGGGGAUCAGUGAAGGAAGAGAAGGCCAGCAGAUCACUGAGAGUGCAACCCCACCCUCCACAGGAAAUUGCCUCAUGGGCAGGGCCACAGCAGAGAGACACAGCAUGGGCAGUGCCUUCCCUGCCUGUGGGGGUCAUGCUGCCACUUUUAAUGGGUCCUCCACCCAACGGGGUCAGGGAGGUGGUGCUGCCCCAGUGGGCCAUGAUUAUCUUAAAGGCAUUAUUCUCCAGCCUUAAGUAAGAUCUUAGGACGUUUCCUUUGCUAUGAUUUGUACUUGCUUGAGUCCCAUGACUGUUUCUCUUCCUCUCUUUCUUCCUUUUGGAAUAGUAAUAUCCAUCCUAUGUUUGUCCCACUAUUGUAUUUUGGAAGCACAUAACUUGUUUGGUUUCACAGGUUCACAGUUAAGAAGGAAUUUUGCCUCUGAAUAAAUAGAAUCUUGAGUCUCAUGCA